ACACCCGGUUGGGCUCUGCUGCUCCCUUCUGGGUUCCGAGGCCCAAGCCCUUGGCAGUGUUUGUGAGUGGAAGGGAGGUCACGCUAUCGUCCGCGGCCCCAGCAGCCCUGUGCCCUCGUUGGAUCCCGCGACGCGGCUCCUUUAAGAGCCUCGCGGGUCGCCCGCCGCUAGGUCGCUCCCCGGCCAUGCGGGCGCUGCGGGCCGGCCUGACCCUGGCGUCGGGCGCGGGGCUGGGUGCGGUCGUCGAGGGCUGGCGGCGGCGGCGGGAGGACGCGCGGGCGGCGCCGGGACUGCUGGGCCGGCUGCCCGUGCUGCCCGUGGCGGCGGCAGCCGAGUUGCCCCCUGUGCCCGGGGGACCCCGCGGCCCGGGCGAGCUGGCCAAGUACGGGCUGCCGGGGCUGGCGCAGCUCAAGAGCCGCGAGUCGUACGUGCUGUGCUACGACCCGCGCACCCGCGGCGCGCUCUGGGUGGUGGAGCAGCUGCGACCCGAGCGUCUCCGCGGCGACGGCGACCGGCGCGAGUGCGACUUCCGCGAGGACGACUCGGUGCACGCGUACCACCGUGCCACCAACGCCGACUACCGCGGCAGUGGCUUCGACCGCGGUCACCUGGCCGCCGCCGCCAACCACCGCUGGAGCCAGAAGGCCAUGGACGACACGUUCUACCUGAGCAACGUCGCGCCCCAGGUGCCCCACCUCAACCAGAAUGCCUGGAACAACCUGGAGAAAUAUAGCCGCAGCUUGACCCGCAGCUACCAAAACGUCUAUGUCUGCACAGGGCCACUCUUCCUGCCCAGGCUCGGGAUGGAGUCCAGGCCUCAUCACCUAGUUCCUUGGUGCUGUGGGCAAAUGACCUGUGUCCCCCUCUGCAAAACCUGUGACCUCUUGGUUGAUGUCACAUGCUUCCCCAGGGCCUGGUCCAUGGACAGAGGCUGAUGGGAAAUCCUACGUAAAGUACCAGGUCAUCGGCAAGAACCACGUGGCAGUGCCCACACACUUCUUCAAGGUGCUGAUCCUGGAGGCAGCAGGUGGGCAAAUUGAGCUCCGCACCUACGUGAUGCCCAACGCACCUGUGGAUGAGGCCAUCCCACUGGAGCGCUUCCUGGUGCCCAUCGAGAGCAUUGAGCGGGCUUCGGGGCUGCUCUUUGUGCCAAACAUCCUGGCGCGGGCAGGCAGCCUCAAGGCCAUCACGGCGGGCAGUAAGUGAGGGUGGAGCCCAGUGAGACUGUGGGUGUGUGCAGGCCGGGGAGUAUUAAAGGUGGUGAUUUUUGGA